UUGUUUAUUCUCUGUCUCUCUCUUUUUCUCUCUUUUUUUUUUUUUUUUUUUUUUUUUGAGAGGGAGUCUCACUCUGUCGCCCAUGCUGGAGUUCUGUGGCACAGUCUUGGCUCACUGCAACCUCUGCCUCCCAGGUUCAAGGGAUUCUCCUGCCUCAGCCUCCCGAGUAGCUGGGAUUACAGGUGCCUGCCACCACGCCCGGCUAAUUUUUGUGAUUUUUUUUUUAGUAGAGACGAGGUUUUACUACGUAGGCGAAGUUGGUCUCGAACUCCUGACCUCAGAUGAUCCACCCGCCUCAGCCUCCCAAAGUGCUGGGAUUACAGGCGUGAGCCACCGCACCUGGCCUGUUUAUUCUCUUAAGAGAGAAAAUGAGGGGAUUAGUGGACUGUAGUUCUGGACAAGGUGGAAAACUCUUAAAGUGGAAGUAUUGGGGCAAGUGCUCUGACAGGCUAGGAUGGUGCAGUCAGUCCCUUCACCCAGAAAUCAGUAGAAUGUUAACAGUUCAGACUCAAACCUUGUGAAAAACAGGUUCUAGAAAGGAAAUCCCUCACAGCAACUGGCACCAUAAUCAAGACAGAAUUUUUGCAGAAUAAAUAGAGUUACCUGCUUUCAGCCCCAGGUCGUAGCUAUUGUCUGCCCUGCUGAUAUGUGAUAAUAAUUUGUGAUCCUGUUGUCUUAAAAUGGGGUCACUCAUCUCCAGUAGAAUUAAGUCCACAGUGAAGUUGUCCCCCCAUCCCCAGAGAUAAACAUAUAUGAAUGAACUUACGUGAUAACAACUACUGCUGCCUGGGAUCAUGAGAGACCUGAACUGAACUGAUAGGAAGUGAAAGGUGGCUGAGGUAAUGAGAAUAGACCCAUCUGCAGAGGAUCAUAAAACCAGCAAAGACAAGAUCUUGUCUAAGAUGCCUUCACAAACUUUGUCCAUGAGAACUGUAAGGUCUUCUCCAGACCUGUUGGCUGCUGCUGUGAUCUCUGCCCAAGAGGAGCUUCUGACCAACAUCCAAAGGGCUUCUGGACCCACUGGACUCCUCUGGAGUUGCUCCUUCACAUGUUCCCACUCUCUGUGCGGCCACCAUGGAAGUCGGACCUGCCCUUCUGCCAUGAUUGACUAAAAUCUCAGGAAGCUGGUGAUGAAUGAAAACCUUAGUCCCAAUGGCACUGCACGAGGGGCCAGGAGAGCAGCAGCAUCAUAAGCCACAGGCGUCAGCCUCGAGUUUGACCAGCAGCAGGGGUCGGUGUGUCCCUCUGAAUCUGAGAUCUAUGAGGCAGGAGCUGGGGACAGGAUGGCAGGAGCGCCCAUGGCUGCUGCUGUACAGCCUGCUGAGGUGACUGUUGAAGUUGGUGAGGACCUCCACAUGCACCACGUUCGUGACCGGGAGAUGCCUGAAGCUUUGGAGUUUAACCUUUCUGCCAAUCCAGAGGCAAGCACAAUAUUCCAGAGGAACUCUCAAACAGAUGCUUUGGAGUUUAACCCUUCUGCCAAUCCAGAGGCAAGCACAAUAUUCCAGAGGAACUCUCAAACAGAUGUUGUAGAAAUAAGAAGAAGCAACUGUACAAACCAUGUAUCUACUGUGCGUUUCAGUCAACAAUACAGCUUGUGUUCGACAAUAUUCCUUGAUGACAGCACAGCCAUCCAGCAUUAUCUUACAAUGACAAUAAUAUCUGUGACCUUGGAGAUACCUCAUCAUAUCACACAAAGAGAUGCAGAUAGAUCUUUGAGCAUACCUGAUGAACAGUUACACUCAUUUGCGACAGGGUUUCACCAUGUUGGCCAGGAUGGUCUUGAACUCCUGACCUCGUGAUCCACCCACGUUGGCCUCCCAAAGUGCUGUGAUUACAGGUUUCCACCGUGCACAUUAUGAAGAAAAGAAAUGGAGGUGGGAGUUUAAAUAACUAUUCCUCCUCCAUUCCAUCGACUCCCAGCACCAGCCAGGAGGACCCUCAGUUCAGUGUUCCUCCCACUGCCAACACACCCACCCCCGUUUGCAAGCGGUCCAUGCGCUGGUCCAACCUGUUUACAUCUGAGAAAGGGAGUGACCCAGACAAAGAGAGGAAAGCCCCGGAGAAUCAUGCUGACACCAUCGGGAGCGGCAGAGCCAUCCCCAUUAAACAGGGCAUGCUCUUAAAGCGAAGUGGGAAAUGGCUGAAGACAUGGAAAAAGAAAUACGUCACCCUGUGUUCCAAUGGCGUGCUCACCUAUUAUUCAAGCUUAGGUGAUUAUAUGAAGAAUAUUCAUAAAAAAGAGAUUGACCUUCAGACAUCUACCAUCAAAGUCCCAGGAAAGUGGCCAUCCCUAGCCACAUCGGCCUGCACACCCAUCUCCACCUCUAAAAGCAAUGGCCUAUCCAAGGACAUGGACACCGGGCUGGGUGACUCCAUAUGCUUCAGCCCCAGUAUCUCCAGCACCACCAGCCCCAAGCUCAACCCGCCCCCCUCUCCUCAUGCCAAUAAAAAGAAACACCUAAAGAAGAAAAGCACCAACAACUUUAUGAUUGUGUCUGCCACUGGCCAAACGUGGCACUUUGAAGCCACGACGUAUGAGGAGCGGGAUGCCUGGGUCCAAGCCAUCCAGAGCCAGAUCCUGGCCAGCCUGCAGUCAUGCGAGAGCAGUAAAAGCAAGUCCCAGCUGACCAGCCAGAGCAAGGCCAUGGCCCUGCAGUCGAUCCAAAACAUGCGUGGGAACGCCCACUGUGUGGACUGUGAGACCCAGAAUCCUAAGUGGGCCAGUUUGAACUUGGGAGUCCUCAUGUGUAUUGAAUGCUCAGGAAUCCACCGCAGUCUUGGCACCCGCCUUUCCCGUGUGCGAUCUCUGGAGCUGGAUGACUGGCCAGUUGAGCUCAGGAAGGUUAUGUCAUCUAUUGGCAAUGACCUAGCCAACAGCAUCUGGGAAGGGAGCAGCCAGGGGCAGACAAAACCCUCAGAAAAGUCCACGAGGGAAGAGAAGGAACGGUGGAUCCGUUCCAAAUAUGAGGAGAAGCUCUUUCUGGCCCCACUACCCUGCACUGAGCUGUCCCUGGGCCAGCAGCUGCUGCGGGCCACCGCUGAUGAGGACCUGCAGACAGCCAUCCUGCUGCUGGCACAUGGCUCCCGUGAGGAGGUGAACGAGACCUGUGGGGAGGGAGACGGCUGCACGGCGCUCCAUCUGGCCUGCCGCAAGGGGAAUGUGGUCCUGGCGCAGCUCCUGAUCUGGUACGGGGUGGACGUCAUGGCCCGAGAUGCCCACGGGAACACAGCGCUGACCUACGCCCGGCAGGCCUCCAGCCAGGAGUGCAUCAACGUGCUUCUGCAGUACGGCUGCCCCGACAAGUGUGUGUAGUAUCUGUUUUAUUUGACUGCAGUCUCCUUGGUGCAAAAACAAAAUGGGAAAAAUAAGGAUAACUCAGAAUUUCAAAAGGAAAUCACAAAUUCAGCUAAUAAUAGCAUUUUCAGUACUUUUCGUAAACUAAGUAAAUACACAAAAUGUUGAUUUUUCUGACCAUAAGACGUAUUUUAUGUCCUUUUGCCAAGGUGGAUUUGUUAGUCUCAGGCCCUCCUGGCCACAUUGCCCAAGUCACACAGGCUUCUGUAUUAUGUAUUUAGAUAAAAUGUGUGAAAAUAUAUUUGAAAUAAAGUUCAUAAAUAUGCAUUGAUUUUUGUA